AUGUGUUUAUUGUUAAAAACUUAGGACGAAAGUUAAAAAAAAAAACCCACACUACUUAAUUACAGAGAUCUUCAUUAACAUAAUUCUGUAUUUAUUUUCUAUAGGAAAAUUUUUAAUGCUAACUUUCUAGAACUCAGUCAAAAACUACUGUAAUCAUUUUAAUCAGCUGAUUAAUUUGCUCUAGCAGCUUAAAAUGUUUUUGCUCCAUUUUACUUUUUCUACUGCAUGAUAGAAAAAUUGUUGUUCUGUGAAUGAGAAAGUUAAAAUUUGUGCUCAAUGGCAGGACCCCAGAGAGAUGUUUCUGGGAAUUGAGAUUCAGAGGCAGCCUGCAUUCAGCUUUCUUCAGGUUACCUUUAUUAAUGAUGCCCUUGAUCAGUAAGGUGGAUUACUUACCCAUUAACACUUAUUCUACAUCAGCCUUAAUGUUUUAGGGAAAAUAUAUUUACUAAGCUGUUUGUGUACAGGAGUAUCACACAGUAGAUGAAGCACUUAUGUUUCUGGAAAAAAAGAGAUAAAUUAGGAAGCUUUCAGAUUUGUUUAUAAAAGAAAUAUGAGGCUAGGAAAGAAGCAUGAUGACUUUUGUGAUACACACAGUGAGUCAGCAACCCAUUUUCCAGAAGUUAGCAGCUGCAUUUUUUUCCAUUGAGGGCAAAACAUAAUAUAUGGGUAUAACUUUAGUGCUAGCUAAUUACUUCUAUUGGUGCUUAAAAAAAUUAAAAUCAACAAGGAGAAAUCUACCCAAACUGAUCCAAUAUACACUGAGCUAAUGAAGGAAGGUGGUGUACUUUUUGUGGGGUAGUAUUUUUAUUUUGAUUAUGUUGAAGUGGUAGAGAAAGAAGGGGAGAGAUCUGGGGGUCUGAGAGUCAGAGGAGGCUACAAAUGAUAUAGCAAAGCAAAUAACUAGAUUAUGAAUCUUUUGAAAUCAUGCAGGGGAACAAAAUAUUGUUACUGCCUUAUCAAAAAGUAUUUUCUCCUGUAUAAUUUAAAAAAUCAAGAAGGUGUCAACCUUAAAAAUCGUAUCAUUGAAUAUAGUAAGUCCCUUUUUUUUUGUUAAUAUAGCCUGUUGGUUUAGUAGAUUUUUGCAUCUUAUUGUCUGAUUUUUAUACCAUACAGACUAAUAAAAAUUAGUUUAUGCACUUAUUUGUUACUUUUAUUUCUGAAUAGAUAAUACAGUCAGCGUAGUAUAAAAGGUUAGACAGUGAUGUCUGAAUUCUACUCCUUCCCCUAGCUAGUUUCCUUCCCAGAGGCAACCAUUGUUACUGUUACCAUGUUUUCCUAAAGACAGUUCCUGCAAAUGUUGGCAAAUCUGUGUGUGUUCUCUUUCCUUGUCUCUGUGCCUUCCUUUCUUUUAGGAAUGCUAGCAUACAUACUAUAAUAUUCUGGGUCUGUCUGGUUGUUUUUACUUCAUGUGCUCUGUAGAUUAUUUCAGUACACCAAGAGCUUCCCCAUUGUUUCAUAGUUGGGUAGUAUUCUGUUGUAUUAUUAUGCCAUGAUGUAUUUAAGGAAUAUGCUAUUGGUGGACAUUUAAAAUGUUUCCAGUUUGCUCCUUUGAACAAUGCUGCAGUAUAUAAAGUUGUACAUAUAUGUAGGUUUGUUAAGAAAUAAGUGGAAACCCAUAGCUGAAAGAUGGUUUUAGGAUUGUCCCUGGGAAUUAGAUCUCUAUCAUUGUUUCCCAGUGCUCCUUGGAACCCUCCUCAGGGAAAUAGGCAUCAUUGGAGUAGAAGGCAAAUGGGAUUUCAUGGCCAAAUAAAUUUGGAAAAUGCAGUGUCCUUGAUUAUUCCUUGGAGCUUCCUAAAAUAACUAGCAUGUUAAAGGCUUAACGUGCUCAUGUGGUUUUAAGAACAACAAAAAAACUGCCAAAGAUAAAUUUUCAGGCUCACUUGAGUAUCACAUAUUUGAAGAUGCCUGUUAACAUCUUUCGAGACAGUUUCUGGGAAAAAAUAGUUUGGGAAAUGUUGACCUAUGUGAUUACUACCUGUCUCACCAAUUCCAUAGAUACUGGAAACUAGCUAACUGAGUUUUCAGCUGACAAAUUGCUUGCUUUUGGAGUCAAGUGUCUUGACAUAUGUAGCUUGUUCACCUCUCUGGUCCUAUUGCUUAAAGUGAGAAAUAGCGUAUUUGGAAGGUUGUAUGUCAGGACCAUCUUCUGUUUGUGAGCGCGAGAGAAGGUAGGAUCAGAUAUCUUGGGUGGAGCCCAGUCUCCAGCUCAAGACUUGAGUUGUAAAAAUCGUGUUGUAUUGUGGGACAAAAAUCAAGCAGUUCAUUUUGGCUAGGGUUUAGGGGAUAGAAAUGGGUGGAGGAGAGUCAUAAGGCUUUCUAAAAUAAGCUGCACUACAGCAGAAGUUGCAGUUGGGAGUUCUGUUGUAGAAAAUGGAGAGGAAAGCAAUAGAUUUUUUUCCCUCCAGUUUGCAUUGGUUCUCAACCGGGGAUGAUUUUGCUUUCCUGCUAAAGGGGAUGUUUGGCAAUGUCUGGAGACAUUUUUGGUUACCACGACUGGAAAGGUGCUACCAGCAUCUGAAAGUGAGUGAGAAGGUUGGAGGAGCUGAAGGAACCAAGCUAGAUGAUGACUUCAAAGAGAUGGAAAGGAAAGUGGAUGUCACCAGCAGGGCUGUGAUGGAAAUAAUGACUAAAACAAUUGAAUACCUUCAACCCAAUCCAGCUUCCAGAGCUAAGCUCAGCAUGAUCAACACCAUGUCAAAAAUCCGUGGCCAGGAGAAGGGGCCAGGCUAUCCUCAGGCAGAGGCGCUGCUGGCAGAGGCCAUGCUCAAAUUUGGAAGAGAGCUUGGAGAUGAUUGCAACUUUGGCCCAGCACUUGGUGAGGUCGGGGAGGCCAUGCGGGAACUGUCGGAGGUCAAAGACUCUUUGGACAUAGAAGUGAAGCAGAACUUCAUUGACCCUCUUCAGAAUCUUCAUGACAAAGAUCUUAGGGAAAUUCAACAUCAUCUAAAGAAGUUGGAGGGUCGACGCCUGGAUUUUGAUUAUAAGAAGAAACGACAAGGCAAGAUUCCGGAUGAAGAGCUUCGUCAAGCUCUAGAGAAAUUUGAUGAGUCUAAGGAAAUUGCUGAGUCAAGCAUGUUCAAUCUCUUGGAGAUGGAUAUUGAACAAGUGAGCCAGCUCUCUGCACUUGUGCAAGCUCAGCUGGAGUACCACAAGCAGGCAGUCCAGAUCCUGCAGCAAGUCACGGUCAGACUGGAAGAAAGAAUAAGACAGGCUUCAUCUCAGCCUAGAAGGGAAUAUCAACCUAAACCACGAAUGAGCCUGGAGUUUCCAACUGGAGACAGUACUCAGCCCAAUGGGGGUCUCUCCCACACAGGCACUCCCAAACCUUCAGGUGUCCAAAUGGAUCAGCCCUGCUGCCGAGCUCUGUACGACUUUGAACCUGAAAAUGAAGGGGAGUUGGGAUUUAAAGAGGGCGAUAUCAUCACACUCACUAACCAAAUUGAUGAGAACUGGUAUGAGGGGAUGCUGCAUGGCCAUUCAGGCUUCUUCCCCAUCAAUUAUGUGGAAAUUCUGGUUGCCCUGCCCCAUUAGGAUGUUAUGCUGGCUGGCUCGCCUCCUCUUGACCCAGAUAGUUACGGUUAACCACUGCUUUGGCAAUGCUGCUUAUAACACAUCCCAAGUGCAGGCCGCAGUGGUCCACGUCAUCCAGCCCCACCAAGUGACUUUGGUUGACUUGUGGGCUCCCACAGGAGUCAUGGUGAUGGAUGAUAUCCUCUUAGCCUGGUGGGCGUGGCAUGUGCUUUUUAAAACAUCAUCUGAGACCAGCCAGUAGUCACAGAACUGCUGUUUACACAGUUCUCAGGAGGCUGUGGUUUCUUAGAAUAUGACCAUGAGCCAUUUCACAGAAAAACCAUCCCACCGAAGAUAUUGUCUAUCACCCCAGGGGCCAUCUGAAGGUCUCUUUGCAUUUCUCCAUGCAAAGAGGAGAAAGCUUUUGCUUUCACACUGUCCCUUCCCAAAUAUGUGAGUCAUGGAAUUGUCAAAGUAAGCCUUCCCUCACCAGCAAAUUGUCUCCUGAUCUGAAUGAAUUUGUCUCUUAAUGCAUCCAUAGAAAAGUGUUAAUUGUGGGUUCAAAGCAUUCUCUGCAAAUAGGCAUCUCAGCUCCUCACACUUAUGGCUAUUUCUGACGUAUAGCCAGUUUUCUUCCCUCCUUGCUAUUAAAGCCAGAGCGGUAAUUCCAAAUUAUUUUUCAGUAAGACAGUUAAUCAGCAUUAUUGUGAGAGGGACUGAAAAGAAAUUCUCCAUUAUGAGGAAUUGGGAAGAAAUCUGGUAUCCAAGCUUAAAUUUCUUGCUAUACAGAAACUAUGUAUGUAUUUAGGCUAUUUCUGAAGGGCACAGGGAAGGGGGAACAAAUAUCUUCACUUCAGUUUUAUUUGUGAAUUACAUGUUUCAUGAAUCCAUUUGGCACAGAGACACAAGGAAGAAAACACUAGUAACCAUCUUUCCACUAGUUCAUAUACUGAGAAACAGUAAAUACCUUUCCUUUCCACUUUUACCCUGUGUUCUUUGAACAUCAUUUGUGCAGAUUCUGCCCUCAAUGAGGACCAAAUAAAGAUGAUUUUUGUGCUUAGCAGUUUAAGGUAUAUGGCUGCAUAUGCAAAACUCUUUCCCAAUUCAGUCGCUACUUUUACUUCUGCCCUUUCUAUCCAUCGUCUUCAUUUUGUGUGUACAGUGCUGUGUGUAAGCUUAUCAGUGUGUUUUUUUAUUUGUAUCAGUCAUGAAAGUCCUGUUAGGUAUGCAGAGUUCUAUUUAUCUAGCUGUACAGACUCUUUCAGAGGUUUAACGUGCUGCUUCCGAUGUGCCACCUGCAGUAGUGGAUCAUGUGGAGUGAAAGGCAAAUCUUACUGCUUAAUGUAUAAACUCUCACCACAGGAAGCAUCGCUGUUUCCAAUAAAUAUUGCUGAAGACAGAA